GAGACGCCAGAUGUGAGUUGAGGUGCCAGACGUGAGUUGAGGUGCCAGACGUGGCGGCGUUGGGUACCCAGGACCCUCGGACGGGUCUGCUGCGGCUUGCUGGGGGUCCACUCCAGACCCUGUUCGCCUGGGUAUCACCAGUGGAGUUUGCAGAACAGCAAAGAUUGCUGCUUGCUCCUUCCUCCAGAAGCUUCUUCCCACAGUGGCAUCAACCUGAUUGAUGUCAGCCGGAACUCUCCUGCAUGAGGUGUCUGGCGACCCCUGAUGGGAAGUCUCACCCAGUCAAGAAGCACGGGACUGGAAGGGGGACCUCCUUACGGAGGCAGACUGACUGUCCCUUAGCAGAGCUGGUGCACUGUAUUGGAGGAAUAACCCUCCUUGGGAUCAGCUGGUCUCUUCAGAGCCAGCAGGCAGGAAAGAUUAAGUCUGCUGAACCUCGGACCAUGGCCGCCGCUCCCCCGAGGUGCUCUGUCCCAGGGAGAUUAGAGUUCUUGUCUGUAAGCCCCUGACUGUAGCUACUGGAAUUCCUGCAGGGAUGCCCUCCAGGUGAGGAGGGAUGGCUUCGGGUCCCACCUAGGAAGCAGUCUGGCCACGAUCUGCAACAGCCACUUUGCUGCGUUGUGGGGAAUUCCACCCAGUCCAAACCUCCUAGUCUCCUUAGCACUGUCAGGGGAAAACCUCCAACUAAAGCCUCAGUAAUGACGGUCGCCCCUCCCCCUGGGAACUGAGUUGUCCCAGGCGGACUCCAGACUGCUGUGCCGGCAGCGGGGAUUUCAAGCCAGUGGUUCUUAGCUUGCGGGGUUUCCGUGGGAGUGGGACCCUCUGAGCGAGACCACUUGGCUCCCUGGCUACAGCCCCCUUUCCACAGAAGUGGACAUUUCUCCUGCCUCACUGGAGUUCCAGGUGCUGCCGGAGUAUGUAAAAAUUCCUGCAGCUCAGUGCCUGCCCAAACAGCCGCCGACGGGAGCAGCUGUCAUUGGUCUGCCCAGUUUUGUAUUUGAGACCCAGGGCACUGGUGGUUGUAGGCUCCCGAGGGGAUCUGCUGAUCUGUGGAUUGCAAAAAUCUGUGGGAAAAGCUUAGUACCCUUGGUGGGUAGCACUGUCCCUCACCACUUCCCUUGGCUGGGGAGGGAGGUCCCCCUGCCCUGUGCAGUUCCUGGGUGAAGCAAUACCCUGCUUCUUCUCGCUCUCUGUGGGUCAUGCCGACCAUCUAGUCAGUCCCAGUGAGAUGAACUGGGUAUCUCAGUUGGAAAUGCAGAAAUCACCCACAUUCCUCGUUCCUCUCGCUGGCAGCUGCAGACCAGAGCUGCUUCUAGUCGGCAGUCUUGGCCCCUCCCCGCCGAGGUAAGUUUAAUAAGUCUUCUAAAUUUGUCCUUGCCAUAAUGAUCAGUGAUGAUCUGUCUUUUAAUAAGUUAAAUGCUUUCCAGACUUCAAGACUCUCACCCACAUCAAAAAUAAAAUUAUAUAUCGGCCAUAUUACCAGGAUUUUAGAAUGUUGUAUUUUAUCCUCUAAUUAUAGGUCAAAUAACUAAGGUAGAAAGGAGUAAAGCAACUUCCAUGUAUGUAGUGAGGAUGUUGGGGGGUCUGGGACUAAAAUUCUGCCUUGGGAUUCCCAAGAGGUUGGUGAUUAUGAUUUUUGUACUCUUAGACACAAAAUAAAAUAACAUUCUGUUUUGUUCCUCUGCUUACCCUAUUCAGUUCUCUAAACUACAAAAUCUCUGCUUAUCAAAAUAAGUUGGAUUGUCAAUUUGUUGAGCUCAGCAAAUGCAUUUCCUGAGCCCUUGUGAGUAAAGCUCUGUGCUGGUUACACUGCGUAACUAGUGAUACAGAGGAUGAGUAGAGCAUUCUUUCCUGAAAAGAGCUUAAGAUUUCUGUGCCCAGGUCAGCUUGGGUUGCCUGUAAGUGAGAAAAUUGACAGCCAACACCCACAGGCUUAUUCUGAUAAAAUGGGAGAUGAUAAUAAAUGGUGGGGUUUUUUUCUUUUUCUAUUUUCUUUUUUUUCGAGAUGAUGUCUUGCCACGUUCCCCAGGCUGGUCUUACCUCCUGGGCUCAGGCAUUCUUCCCUCCUUGGCCUCCCACAGUGCUGGGAUUACAGCGUGAGCCACACACCUGGCCUUGUGAAUGGUGGUUCUGUCAAGACUGGGCUUUCAACCUCCCAAGGAUUCUGGUCAAACAGCCUCAGGAGAAUCUUCUGCAGAGAGUGUCUGCCUGCCAACUGUCAGAGCUGAGUGUCACAGAAUCUUGGCAUGGGUCUCCUCCCUCUGUUCCAUUUCACAGAUUACAUGUUGUUAGUAGGAACAUCACCAGAAGGAGCAUGAGGAUGUUCCUUCUAAGAACUAGGAAAGAUAUAAUAAUGCUGCUGGCUGGGCUAUUUUAAAAAAGUAAUCAAGGGCCUUCUCAGAAAGUGAUUUUAGGAACUAUAAUGCAUAGAUGGGAUCAAUUAUAGUGUAAGAACUGAAAAAUUAUUGCACUGAACAGCACCUAACAGCUUCUGGAGAAAACAUAUUUCCCAACUGACCCUGAUGAUGGACUUAAAUACCAAAAAACAGAGAGAACCACUAACUUCCAUUGUCUUGCAGAAACAGGAGAACCUUAAUGCACUUAAAGCUGGAAAAAUGUCUCUGCCUCUAAGGCCAUGCAGUGAAACAGAUUGCAUGGUAGGUGACAUAGGCAGGGGCAGAAUGGAGUUUAUGACAAUGGCCAUAAGAUGAUGAAAAAAAUUAUUUGGGGCCUUUGAAGCAGCAGAUGAGCUGGCUCAGAGGAAAGUUGCACAACUGUAGAAAAACAACUUUUGCAAAAUUUUCCUCCACUCAGUGGGCACUACAUACUUAUUCUAGGAUUUGCAUUCAUUCUUUCACAGACUGUUUACUUAUUGGCUUGGGCCUACAAUGACUUUUCUGAGAGAGGUGAGGGAUUAGCACAACAGCACACACACGCCUGAAAGAAAUAGUGAAUUUCUAAUUUUCAGAUUUUAGUCUCUGACCUAACCAAAGAAUUGACCAUUGUAGAUUUUAUCUAUUAAUAAUAUUAAUGAUGCUCACAAAUAUGAAGAUUUAAGUACAUCUUAUGAUAAUAAGAGAUGCUUUCAAAAAAAAAGAAAUGGUAGAACUGUAGUCCAGGGAUGUUAAUAAAAGUGGCAAAUAACAUUACAUCAUCUUUUUUAAAAAAGAAGAUGAGGUCUCACUGUGUUGUCCAGGCUCAUCUCAAACUCCCAGACUCCAGUGAUCCUCCUGCCUCAGCCUCCCAAAAUGCUGGAAUCACAAGCUUGAGCCAUCACCUUCAGCCCAUAUCAUCUUAACAUCCAAUAGGAACAGUCAACUGACCCACUGGGAAUGUGACCUUGUGAAUCACCCAGAAAUGAGGUGUCUGACAUCCUGAGACCUGGACCCAUUUCAAGGAGCUUUGGGAAGAGCCCAGAUCACUGAUGGAAUUGGACAGUGCGUGGAAAUGGUUCAGCAGGACGAGGUCCCUGGCUCUACCUCUUCUGCCACAAACGUCAGCAUGGUGGUAUCUGCCGACCCUUUGUCCAGCGAGAGGGCAGAGAUGAACAUCCUAGAAAUCAACCAGGAAUUGCGCUCGCAGCUGGCAGAGAGCAAUCAGCAGUUCCGAGACCUCAAAGAGAAAUUCCUUAUAACUCAAGCUACUGCCUACUCCCUGGCCAACCAGCUGAAGAAAUACAAGUGUGAAGAGUACAAAGACAUCAUAGACUCUGUGCUGAGGGAUGAACUGCAGUCCAUGGAGAAGCUGGCAGAGAAGCUCAGGCAAGCUGAGGAGCUCAGGCAGUAUAAAGCCCUGGUUCACUCUCAGGCAAAAGAGCUGACCCAGUUACGGGAGAAGUUACGGGAAGGGAGAGAUGCCUCCCGCUGGCUGAACAAGCAUCUGAAAACCCUCCUCACUCCUGAUGACCCUGACAAGUCCCAGGGUCAGGACCUCCGAGAGCAGCUGGCUGAGGGGCACAGGCUGGCAGAGCACCUUGUUCACAAGCUGAGCCCAGAAAAUGAUGAAGAUGAAGAUGAGGAUGAAGACGACAAAGACGAGGAGGUUGAGAAAGUACAGGAAUCACCUGCCCCCAGAGAGGUGCAGAAGACUGAAGAAAAGGAAGUCCCUCAGGACUCACUGGAGGAAUGUGCUGUCACUUGUUCAAAUAGUCACAACCCUUCUAACUCCAACCAGCCUCACAGGAGCACCAAAAUCACAUUUAAGGAACACGAAGUCGACUCUGCUCUGGUUGUAGAGAGUGAACACCCUCAUGAUGAAGAGGAGGAAGCUCUAAACAUUCCCCCAGAAAAUCAAAAUGACCAUGAGGAGGAGGAGGGGAAAGCGCCAGUGCCCCCCAGACACCAUGACAAGUCCAACUCUUACCGGCAUCGUGAAGUCUCUUUCUUGGCAUUGGAUGAACAGAAAGUUUGCUCCGCUCAGGAUGUUGCCAGGGAUUACUCCAAUCCCAAAUGGGAUGAAACCUCACUUGGCUUCCUCGAAAAGCAAAGUGAUCUUGAAGAGGUGAAAGGACAAGAAACAGUUGCUCCCAGGCUCAGCAGGGGACCGCUGAGAGUGGACAAGCAUGAAAUCCCCCAGGAGUCACUGGAUGGAUGUUGCUUGACUCCUUCCAUCCUUCCUGACCUGACUCCCUCCUACCACCCUUAUUGGAGCACUUUGUACUCUUUUGAAGACAAGCAAGUCAGCUUGGCUCUUGUAGACAAAAUUAAAAAGGAUCAAGAGGAGAUAGAAGACCAAAGCCCACCAUGCCCCAGGCUCAGCCAGGAGCUGCCAGAGGUGAAGGAGCAGGAAGUCCCAGAGGACUCUGUGAAUGAAGUUUACUUGACUCCCUCAGUUCACCAUGACGUGUCUGACUGCCACCAGCCUUAUAGCAGCACCUUGUCCUCAUUGGAGGAUCAGCUUGCCUGCUCUGCUCUGGAUGUAGCCUCCCCCACCGAGGCGGCCUGUCCCCAAGGGACUUGGAGUGGAGACUUGAGCCACCACCGGUCAGAGGUUCAAAUUUCACAGGCACAGCUGGAACCAAGCACCCUGGUGCCCAGUUGUCUGCGACUACAGCUGGAUCAAGGGUUCCACUGUGGGAACGGCUUGGCCCAGCGGGGCCUUUCCUCCACCACCUGCAGCUUCUCAGCCAAUGCUGAUUCUGGGAACCAAUGGCCCUUCCAAGAGCUGGUUUUAGAGCCCUCUCUGGGGAUGAAGAACCCUCCCCAGCUGGAAGAUGAUGCACUUGAAGGCUCAGCAAGCAACACACAAGGGCGUCAAGUCACUGGCCGGAUUCGUGCCUCCCUUGUCCUGAUACUGAAGACCAUCAGAAGAAGACUCCCGUUCAGCAAGUGGAGACUGGCAUUCAGAUUCGCUGGCCCGCAUGCUGAGAGUGCAGAGAUACCAAAUACUGCUGAAAGGAUGCAAAGGAUGAUAGGAUGAAAGAAUGUCACAAAAAGCAGCUUUUCCACUUGAUAAAAACAACUAAAACAGCAAAGCAAGUUUAAGUCCAAACACAAUACUGCAGGGGUCCUUCACUGAGGAUUGAAUUUCAGACACAGAAUACUCUUGAUGACUUCAAGCCACUAUGCUCCUUUGAUUUGAGAAGCCACAUUCCAUCCCCCUCCAAUUGUGAUCAACACCUAGGGAGACCAAUGCCCAGAUGGACAAAUAGCAUUGACUGGCGUUAGCCCUGUUUCUCAAUUCCCAUCAUGUAGAGAACAGGAGUCCGCAGCUGCUGGCAGGAGACAGCAUGUCAGCCGGGACUCUGCCAGGGCAGAGUAUGAGCAAUGCCAUGUUCUUGCUGAAAACGUUUAGCCUGAGUUUCAUAGGAGGUAACCCUCAGAUAACUGCAGAAUGUAGAACAUUGAACAGGACAACUGACAUGUCUCCUUCAAACAGUCCAUGUCACCACCAAGAAAACAACAAAAAGGAGAAGAGACAUUUUGAGUUCAAAAAGAGUAAAAAGCCUAUGCAGCUUAUGCUUUUUUAGUCAUUUUGAACCCAAAACAUCUCCUUAUCUUUUUGUUGUUGUCAUCGAUGGUGGUGACAUGGACUUGUUUGUGGAGGACGGGUCAGCUCUCUGGCUCAAUGGUCUACAUUCUGAAGUUAUCUGAAAAUGUCGUCAUGAUUAAAUUCAGCCUAAACAUUUUGCCAGGAACUCUGCAGAGUCCAUGCUGUGAGCUUCCUACCUCAGCCCAUCUGCAGGCAGAGAAGGCCCAGUGUGUCCAUCCCCAGUGCGGUGAUACUAGGAUGUUCACUUGGUCAAGGAGGGGUCUAGGAGCUCUGUCCCUUGUAAAGACACCUUAUUUAUAAUUAAAUUGGAAAGUGGUUUGAAAUAGUAUAAAUAUCCUGUAUUCUAACAAUCUUCUUCUGAGUAUUUUAUCAUCAAUUAAUCACCCCUGCCUGUGUCAGUUAUUAUAUUUAUGUUUUUACAUUGGAAAUUGUCUUCUCAAAAUUUUACUAUGUACUUGUUUUUGCUGGCAUUCUGUCGUAAAAAGGAACAUUCCCUGCCCAAAGUUUGACUUUCAUCCAAAAUUAAUUUUAGUCCAUUAAAGUUAAAAUGUUAAAGUUUUAAAUCACUUUAAUUAAAUUUUUUUGCCUAUCACCCUGGACUAGUGAAUUUUUCACAUACAAUGUUUUAAGCUUUUAUUUUAUUAUUGGUUUUCAUGGAUAAGAAUAUAGAUUAAUAAAAACAUUCUUAUUUACCUGUUUAUAUUCUAAA